AGGGUUGGGUGCGCCGCUGAACGGAUGGCUGAGGGAGCCCCGCGGAUCGUUUAGGAAAGCCGGCCAGGCAUUCCAGAAAACAGCUGCAAACCCUGAGAGAUAUGGCUGGAUUGUUGACCUCCUGGAGUAGUUAGGCCUUUAUUUUUAGUUGCAAAAUUAUCAUCUGAUGCCAUCAAACUGUCUGUGUAAUUUAAUCAGUCUCUUAAAUCAGCAUUGUCAGUUACAGAGAAGCCUUGAGACAGAUGAUUGGAAGCGGGUAUAGAUCUGAGCAGUCGUUACAGUCUGAUAUAUGGGAUGAGAACACAGUGGAUCUGUGUUUGGGUACCUCCACCUCUUUUUGAGUGCAUGAUUGUACCUGCAUUAGUUAUCAGCUGAUCGUCGUGUGUUGCCACCCAUUCAUGUCAAGAUGACUAAGUUUGGAUUUUUGCGAUUGUCCUAUGAGAAGCAGGACACACUUUUGAAGCUUCUCAUUCUGUCAAUGGCUGCUGUAUUAUCCUUCUCCACUCGUCUGUUUGCUGUCCUGAGAUUUGAAAGUGUUAUCCAUGAGUUUGAUCCGUACUUUAAUUAUCGGACUACCAGGUUCCUGGCUGAGGAGGGGUUUUAUAAAUUCCAUAACUGGUUUGAUGACCGAGCCUGGUACCCUUUGGGACGAAUCAUUGGAGGAACAAUUUACCCAGGUUUAAUGAUCACCUCUGCUGCAAUCUACCAUGUACUCCAUUUUUUCCACAUCACCAUCGACAUUCGGAAUGUCUGUGUGUUCCUGGCCCCUCUCUUCUCCUCCUUCACCACCAUCGUCACGUACCACCUUACCAAAGAGCUCAAGGAUGCAGGGGCUGGGCUUCUUGCUGCUGCCAUGAUUGCUGUAGUUCCUGGAUAUAUCUCCCGAUCUGUGGCUGGCUCCUAUGAUAAUGAAGGGAUUGCCAUCUUUUGCAUGCUACUCACCUACUACAUGUGGAUCAAGGCAGUAAAGACUGGUUCCAUCUGUUGGGCAGCUAAGUGUGCCCUUGCUUAUUUCUACAUGGUCUCGUCAUGGGGAGGUUAUGUGUUCCUGAUCAACUUAAUUCCUCUCCACGUCCUCGUGCUGAUGCUCACAGGCCGUUUCUCUCACCGGAUCUAUGUGGCCUACUGUACUGUUUACUGCCUGGGCACUAUACUUUCUAUGCAGAUCUCCUUUGUGGGUUUCCAGCCUGUCCUUUCAUCAGAGCACAUGGCAGCCUUUGGGGUCUUUGGUCUCUGCCAGAUCCAUGCCUUUGUGGAUUACCUGCGCAGCAAGUUGAAUCCACAACAAUUUGAAGUUCUUUUCCGGAGCGUCAUCUCUCUGGUAGGCUUUGUCCUUCUCACCGUGGGAGCUCUCCUCAUGCUGACAGGAAAAAUAUCUCCCUGGACGGGGCGUUUCUACUCGCUGCUGGAUCCCUCUUAUGCUAAGAACAACAUCCCCAUCAUUGCUUCUGUGUCUGAGCAUCAGCCCACAACCUGGUCCUCAUACUAUUUUGACCUGCAGCUCCUCGUCUUCAUGUUUCCAGUUGGCCUCUAUUACUGCUUUAGCAACCUGUCUGAUGCCCGGAUUUUUAUCAUCAUGUAUGGUGUGACCAGCAUGUACUUUUCAGCUGUAAUGGUGCGUCUAAUGCUAGUGUUGGCACCUGUUAUGUGCAUUCUCUCUGGCAUUGGAGUCUCCCAGGUGCUGUCCACAUACAUGAAGAAUCUGGACAUAAGUCGUCCAGACAAGAAGAGCAAGAAGCAACAGGAUUCCACCUACCCUAUUAAGAAUGAAGUGGCAAGUGGGAUGAUACUGGUCAUGGCUUUCUUUCUCAUCACCUACACCUUUCAUUCAACCUGGGUGACCAGUGAGGCCUACUCUUCUCCGUCCAUUGUACUAUCUGCCCGUGGUGGGGAUGGCAGUAGGAUCAUAUUUGAUGACUUCCGAGAAGCAUAUUAUUGGCUUCGUCAUAAUACUCCAGAGGAUGCGAAGGUCAUGUCCUGGUGGGAUUAUGGCUAUCAGAUUACAGCUAUGGCAAACCGAACAAUUUUAGUGGACAAUAACACAUGGAAUAAUACCCAUAUUUCUCGAGUAGGGCAGGCAAUGGCGUCCACAGAGGAAAAAGCCUAUGAGAUCAUGAGGGAGCUCGAUGUCAGCUAUGUGCUGGUCAUUUUUGGAGGCCUCACUGGGUAUUCCUCUGAUGAUAUCAACAAGUUUCUUUGGAUGGUCCGGAUUGGAGGGAGCACAGAUACAGGCAAACAUAUCAAGGAGAAUGACUAUUAUACUCCAACUGGGGAGUUCCGUGUGGACCGUGAAGGUUCUCCAGUGCUGCUCAACUGCCUCAUGUACAAGAUGUGUUACUAUCGCUUUGGACAGGUUUACACAGAAGCCAAGCGUCCUCCAGGCUUUGACCGUGUCCGAAAUGCUGAGAUUGGGAAUAAAGACUUUGAGCUUGAUGUCCUGGAGGAAGCAUAUACCACAGAACAUUGGCUGGUCAGGAUAUACAAGGUAAAGGACCUGGAUAAUCGAGGCUUGUCAAGGACAUAAAUGUCACGUCCAGCUCUGAUAUGCUUCGCACUGAGCACAUCACAUUUAGGACGUUGAAGAUUUUUUUUUUUUUUUUUUUUUAAUAUGCAGUUUGUAAGAACAAAACUGGAUGGCAUCAGAAUUGUCUGGAAGUUUUGUCUUGGGCAGUAUGGGCUGGGCCAAAUGAAAUGAUUUUUAUAAUUCUAAACAGGUUACCAAAUGAAAUGUCAUGGCUUUACUUUGGUCAAUUAAAGGGGGGAAUUUUUUUAAAAAAUGUGCCUUAUUUGUUUUGACUUAUAACUGAUUUGAGGGAGGCAAAAGCUAUGCUAGGCUGCCAGAAGGACAUAAGCAGACCUUGUCCAUUCUCUUAGCUCCCUAAAUUAGCCAAAUAGAGACUUCUUUCUCAAAUCAGGAAAACUAUCAAAGACCAAUUCAGAUCCUACAUUUACAGACAGUUUUGUCAUAACCCUUUGCAUUGCAGCACCUAGUACAAUUCCUUGGAAACAGCGUGGCUCAAUAAAUUUUUAUUGAAUGAAUAAAUGUGGGACCAGAAGAGUGCUAGAAGAGUGCCUUUCUGGGCUACUAUGUCUCUGUUCUCAAUGUCUUUUAUCCUUAGACGCUCUUUGACUUUAUAAAUCAGCAGUUUUGAAGACUCAAGACAAACAGUGAAAUUAUUGGUUUAUCAAUGGAGAGGAAGAAACUCUUCCAGCAUUACAUAUAGAGCUUGAUGGUCAGUAGGUGUUUUUGAAUCAGCUUAAAUAUAAUCAUACAUAUCAAUUUGAAAUGGAGCUUUUCAGUACUCUCACUUAUUCAUGACACAGGAAUGACCCUUUACUCAAAACUCUUGUGGUUGUUCAAAGGUGAGCUUCUUUUUCCCUUAGUCUUAGCCUAUGUGUUGCUGUUGUAUAUUGUUACCAAGUUCAACUACCUAAUUUUGAAGCUCUUUCCAAAUAAGAUACAAAUUAAAAGGGGAAGCAUUGCCAGUAACAGGUCCCUAGAGAGCAGUGCCAGCCUGCCUGCAAGAAAAGAGGAGAAACUUCUUAAAAAGUUUUAAGCCUGGGCAACAUAAGGAGAUUGUUUCUAUGAAAAAUAAAAAUUAGCCAGGUAUGGUGGUGUACACCUGUAGUCCCAGCUACUCGGGAAGAUGAGAUUGGAGGAUCACUUGGGCCUGGGAGGUUGAGGCUACAGUGAACUGUGAUUGUGCCACUGUACUCCAGUCUGGGCGACAGUGAAAUCUUGUCUAAACAAAAACAAUUUAACUGGGAAGCACAGUGGUCCUUGAGGACAUUUAAUAUCAGGACAAAGAGCCUAUGAAUAUAUCACUGAUGUAUAUAAACCCUAAGGCGUUAAUAAAAGCUAACUGUUUAGUGUUAUCCAUUUAAGGGAACAGGAGGAAUUGCAUAACUUUUAGAUUAGUCAUAGUGGUGCUCCUAAGGGAUAUGCUGUUGUAUAUUUGUAUAGCCAGGGCACUUAGCCUUCCAAACCAAUUUAUAUACCAUGUUCUUCAACUGUGGGUGAGAUUUAGCCUCAAGAUUUGAUUUACUAUAUGUAAGUACAUUACUUGAUUUCUAUAAAGAAUCUUUAGUGGAAGAGGUUAUUCUGAAUUAUUUAUCAAUAUGAUUAAUACCAGUUAGAAAUUAUUAAUGAUCUUCCUUUAUACUAUACAUAGGAUAACUUUUAACUUGUCGCUACAGUUGUUGCUCUGAGGAUCUUAAUUUUGUUACUUUCUAGGCUACAUGAAGCUAUCUUUUUAAAAAGUGUACUCUUCAUUUUCACUGUUAUUGUGUACUUAGCAUAAAAAACUCAAAUCUAGGCCAGGUGCAGUGGCUCAUGCCUGUAAUCCCAGCACUUUGGGAGGCUGAAGCAUGCGGAUCACUUGAGCCCAGGAGUUCAAGACCAGCCUGGGCAACAUGGCUAAUGAACACUAAGCAUAGUUUUGAUGUCUUUCAUAUUAAAGACUUUCUCAAAUUCUUGCUAGUCUGCUCCUCUUUAAGAGUGGGACCCUAGGCAGGGCGCAGUGGAUCAUGCCUGUAAUCCCAGCACUUUGGGAGGCCGAGGCAGGCAGAUCACUUGAGGCCAGGAGUUUGAGACCGGCCUGGCAACGUGGGAAAACUCUGUCUCUACUAAAAAUACAAAAAUUAGCUGGGUGUGGGGUACACACCCUGUAAUCUCAGCUACUGGGGAGGCUGAGGCAUGAGAAUUGCCCAGGAGGUGGAGGUUGCAGUGAGCAGACAUCAUGCCACUGCACUCCAACCUGGGAGACAGAGCAAGACUGUCUCAAAAAAAAAAAAAAAAAAAAAAA